GUUUCCGGGAAGAUGGCGGCUGUCGAAGCGGCUGCAGAGCCGGUAACGGUGGUGGCGGCUGUUGGGCCAAAGGCGAAAGACGAAGAGGAGGAGGAAGAGGAGCCGCUGCCACCGUGCGAGGCGGUGCGCUGGGCCCCAGUGGGGGCGGUGGCGGAGGCCCGGCCUGGGGCAACCGCGUUUUUAGAAGAGGCGACGGCCGAGGAGCCUGGCGCGGCCCCGGGCUCCCCGCCGGAUUCGCCGGGCCGGACGCUGCGGCGGCUGCGGGCAGAGCGGCGGCGGCUGGACUCGGCGCUGCUGGCGCUGUCCUCGCACUUCGCGCAGGUGCAGUUCCGCCUGCGCCAGGUGGUGCGCGGGGCGCCGGCGGAGCAGCAGCGCCUUCUGCGGGAGCUCGAAGACUUCGCCUUCCGCGGCUGCCCUCACGUCCUAGGUUACGAAGGGCCCGGCGACCCCGCCAGCGAUGAGGGCGAUGGGCUGCCAGGGGACCGGCCAUGGUUGCGGGGCGAGGACCAGGGCUUGAGUGAGCAGGAAAAGCAAGAGCGUCUGGAAACCCAAAGGGAGAAGCAGAAAGAACUGAUACUGCAGCUCAAGACCCAGCUAGAUGACCUGGAAACGUUUGCCUAUCAAGAGGGCAGUUAUGACUCGCUGCCACAGUCCGUGGUGUUGGAAAGACAGCGGGUGAUCAUAGAUGAGUUAAUAAAGAAACUGGACAUGAAUCUGAAUGAGGACAUCAGUUCCCUGUCCACUGAAGAGCUUCGUCAGCGUGUAGAUGCAGCAGUGGCUCAGAUCGUCAACCCAGCCCGAGUCAAAGAACAGUUGGUUGAGCAACUGAAAACUCAGAUCCGAGACCUUGAGAUGUUUAUCAACUUCAUCCAAGAUGAAGUGGGAAGCCCCUUGCAGACAGGUGGUGGACACUGUGAGUGCAAGGCCGGUGGGAAGACAGGAAAUGGCUGCAGCAGAACAGGCAGCAGCAGAACGCCUCCAGGAAACAGCAAAACAGCAAAGGCAGAGGAUGUGAAGAAAGUCCGGGAGACGGGGCUGCACCUGAUGCGGCGAGCGCUGGCCGUGCUCCAGAUCUUUGCUGUUAGCCAGUUUGGUUGUGCCACAGGCCAGAUCCCUCCAACCCUGUGGCAGAGGGUCCAGGCUGACAGAGACUACUCUCCCUUGCUGAAGAGGCUGGAGGUGUCAGUGGACAGAGUGAAGCAGCUAGCCUUGAGGCAGCAGCCACAUGACCAUGUCAUCACCUCUGCCAACCUCCAGGACCUCUCUCUGGGAGGCAAGGAUGAGCUGACUAUGGCUGUGCGGAAGGAGCUAACGGUGGCUGUGAGGGACCUGCUGGCCCAUGGACUGUAUGCCUCCUCCCCAGGGAUGAGCCUUGUUAUGGCUCCUAUUGCUUGUUUGCUGCCAGCCUUCUCCUCGGCCCCAGAGGCCAUGCACCCGUGGGAGCUCUUUGUAAAGUACUACCAUGCUAAGAACGGCCGUGCUUAUGUGGAAUCCCCAGCCCGGAAGCUCUCCCAGUCCUUCGCCCUUCCUGUUACGGGAGGCACUGUUGUCACCCCCAAACAGAGCCUACUGACAGCCAUCCACAUGGUGCUGACAGAGCAUGACCCUUUUAAGCGCAGUGCAGACUCAGAAUUGAAGGCCUUGGUGUGCAUGGCACUGAAUGAGCAGCGUCUGGUGUCCUGGGUGAACCUCAUCUGCAAGUCCGGGUCACUCAUCGAGCCUCACUACCAGCCCUGGAGCUACAUGGCACACACAGGCUUUGAGAGUGCCCUCAACCUGCUCAGUCGCCUCAGCAGCCUCAAGUUUAGCCUCCCUGUAGAUCUGGCUGUGCGCCAGCUCAAAAACAUCAAAGAUGCCUUUUGAUGAGAGUGCCCUAACCCCAGACAAGCUCCUUGUUCAGUAGGGAUAGAUGUGCUAGUCUUCUAGCAUAGGAGCAAGGAAUCAGAGGUGGGGUUAAAGGCAUUUUUCCCAGACCCUGCUCAGGCAGUCGGCCAAAUGAGUGCAAAGUCUGUUUUCCCCACCAACUUAGCUCUCGGAAAGAUGUGCUGGAGGGACCCUCUUGUUAAGAAGGUUCUGCCAGGCCGGGCGCGGUGGCUCACACCUGUAAUCCCAGCACUUUGGGAGGCCGAGGCGGGCGGAUCACAAGGUCAGGAGUUCGAGACCAUCCUGUCUAACACGGUGAAACCCCAUCUCUACUAAAAAUACAAAAAAAUUAGUCGGACAUGGUGGCAGGCACCUGUAGUCCCAGCUACUCGGGAGGCUGAGGCAGGAGAAUGGCGUGAACCCAGGAGGCGGAGCUUGCAGUGAGCCAAGAUCGCGCCACUGCACUCCAGCCUGGGCGACAGAGUGAGACUCCGUCUCAAAAAAAAAAAGAAGGUUGUACCCACAGUAUACGUGUGGGCACUUGUGCUUGAGCCUGUAUUAAAGGAAUCAGGCCAGGCACAGUGGCUCACGCCUGUAAUCUCAGCACAUUGGGAGGCUGAGGUGGGCGGAUCACCUGAGGUCAGGAGUUCAAGACCAGCCUGGCCAACAUGGUGAAACCCCAUCUCUACUAAAAAUACAAAAAUUAGCUAGGCGGGGUAGUGCAUGCCUGUAAUCCCAGCUACUCAGGAGGCUGAGGCCGGAGAAUCGCUUGAGCCCGAGAGGUGGAGACUGCAGUAAGCCAAGAUCAUGCCAUUGCACUCCAGCCUGGGCAACACAGGGAGACUCCAUCUCAAAAAAAAAAAAAAAAAAAAAAAGACAUUCAACUUGAGGCUCCUGUUAGUUAAGCUAUCUUCUUUCACUUGAAGCAGGUUUGAGAGGCCUAGGCCAGAAUUUAAAUUCCUUUUAUGAAUAGAUUUCCCUUUCUUCCUGACCCCAAGGUCAGAGGAGACUAUAUAUUCCAUGGCUGCCUCUAAGACUAGGAAUAGGAAUAUCUGAAAACAGCAUUUCUAAGGGUGGUAACCACAGGUCGAUUUUAAUACGAGUCCUUUUUCUUGUAGAGGUAAGUAAAAUCUUCCUGACAAGGUAGUCCUCUUUUCAUGGCACAGACAAUGGGCUUUCUGUUUAUGAGGGGUGAGAAGUGAUGUUUGUUACUAUGUUCUCCAGCAAGUAAACAUUCCUCUGCUCACCUCCCAACAAGACUAACAGUCUUUUUAGAAGUAAAUAUAUUCAAGACAAACGAGAAAAUCCUGGCUACCCAAGUCGAGUAUAUACAGGAAUACAAAUCGGUAACCAGCAGCUGUUCCUCAGGUUGUGACUCACUGAGCACCACUUGUCCUGGAGGCUGGAUGAUGGAGGACAUCUGGUUAUAGGUACUGUAGCAGGGAUAGGUGCCACAGGAGGAUAGGAACUACAGCAGAUCGCUGUUUCCAGAACGGGGAGGAGUAUCUCAUUGUGAAACAGACUCUAGAGUGGUUCUAUUUGGUCUUCAGUGUUUUAGCCUCGUUAGUUCAUAUUUGGCAUGCAGCUUGUGGUGAGUACUGUUCUAGGACUGGCCAAAAAUGGGCAAAAUGUAUCACUCCAAACACUACUGAUUCAGCAUUGUUUUCAUGUCUUAAAAUUGCCACCUGCACUUUGUUUCUGCACUAUUAUGUAGUGCAUUUUAACUUAAAUUUUUUCCAGCAACAUGUUACUUAUUUAAGAUACAUUACUGAUAUUUCAUUAUAAUUAGUUCACCUUCCCUGUGAAACAAGAGAAUUGUAAAAUGUUGUGGAAAAUGAUACAUAUGUGGAUGCUAAUGAAAUCAUAGUAUUUUGUGUAGCUUCUCUGAAGACCUUAGAGAUCUGCAGCUUUGGUUUAUAAGUGUUUGGGCCUUAUCAGCCCAUCUGAUCCAGAUCAAUAUUUUUUUGAAAACUGCCUGUAUCCUCUGUCCUCUGUUACGGAUCAUCUCAGCUUUGGUGGUGGUAGUAGGGGUUUUUUGCCUGAAAAAAUUCACUAAAAAGUCCCCUUGGCAUGACCAUCUCCUCCUGCCCACGCCUGUAGUCCCUCCCCACAACAGAUGUCAUCACACAUGCUGCUUUUGGAAUGGAGACCUUUUUUUUUUGAGAUGGAGUCUCGCUCUGUUGUCCAGGCUGGAGUGCAAUGGCGUGAUCUCAGCUCACUGCAACCUCCGCCUCCUGGGUUCAAGCGAUUCUCCUUCCUUAGCCUUCUGAGUAGCUGGGAGUACCGGCGCCUGCCACCACGCCUGGCUAAUGUUUGUAUUUUUAAUAGAGAGGGUUUCACCACAUUUGUCAGGCUAGUCUCGAACUCCUGACCUCAGGUGAUCCACCCACUUCAGCCUCCCAAAGUGCUGGGAUUAUAGGCGUGAGCCACCACACCCAGCCAGGAUUGGCACUUUUAAAUCCACUUGUCUGGAUAUCACUUUGGGUGGUAACUGGUAUAGCCAUAUGGCGUAGCCCAGCGAUCACCCCAGUAUUGCCUUUUUCAAAUCACAAAAACAAAACUUGUAUUAAGGCUUUGUGCUAGCAUUACAGGAAGCAUUUUCAUUUGUCUCAUUCUAAUUAAAUUCUCACUACUUACAAAGUGGGACAGUAUUAUCCCCACUUUACAGCUGAGGAAACUGAACUGCAGAGAGGUUAAAUAUUUUGUCCUGGUUUACAUGAUGAUGGAAGACCUGAGAUUUGGAGUCAAGUUUUCUGAAUCCAGAGCCCACAGUCUAUCUUUUCACUUCAUUGUAUCAUGUUGUUUCUAGAUUUUGGUUUCUCUUUCUCCUUUAUCCACCACCCUCAUUCCUCCCCUCACUUUGGGGAGGAGAAGGUAUUUUCUACACAACUGCCAGAAAUUUCAGCUGCCAAAGGACAAGGCUGCAGGGAGACAGGCCGGCAGCCAUGACUUUCAUGUCUAAGUUCUUGAAACCUAAAUGUGUGUAUCAACUGAGACAACCCAACAAUUCCAUCAGCAUCCCUGCAGUCAGAUAUCUGCUAAGCUCUGAUAUCAUCUGUCAUUACUGAGAACAGAGCUCUGUCCUUCACUUAGGGUGAGACAGGACAAGGGAGGAGAGGCAGGCCAGUCCACCCAGAUCCAAGGAUAUGCAAGAAUGGAAGGGUCAAGAGCCACGGAUAUGUAUGCAGUGGAAAUGUAGGGUGUGUUGUACAAGUAUGAUCUGCAAAGUAUUGUUAAAGCCGUCUAAGGUGCUCUCCAAUCAUUCAUUCACUAUUGAUCACUUAGCAACUGCCUGCCUAGACUAGAUGCUAAAGAAAGAGAAAAGUAAACCUACCCCGUGCCCUCAACAAACACAGUCUAGCAAAGGAGAUACCAUACCAAUUGGAGAUUUGGAGAGACUGUUAAAAUAUAGAUUGCUGGGUCCCA